AUGGAUUCCAGUCUUCUCCAGGCAAUUGAGGAAAUUGAGAAAUUUUUCCAGCAUCUCUCUGAGCGGCAUACAGAACAGGCAGAAACCCCAGAUGCACCAGAACCACAGAACUGUAUGCCUCUGACUGCCCAUGCUGAGGAGAGCCAACAUGAGUCAACCCAGAGCAAGACGAUGCCUCCCUUGGGGUCCACAAUGAUGACUUCUGCAUGCACUAACAUCCCUGGGACAGUUCUCACCCAGGACUUAACAAUGCACCCUCUUAAAGCCCUUGAAGACCUAAGUGAGACUUAUUCCAUGGGCCAGAAAGUGACUUCCUUUGAUCAGGUAAAACACACAGCAGGCUCCCAGAUGACAGAUGUUACUGUCACCCCAAAGUCAUCACCCACUGAUUGCCAGAAGACAACCAUCACUGCAAGCAACAUGACAAUCUCCAAUGAAAGUAGCCAGCUGAACACCCCAAGCAGUGACCAGACCCUCAAUGAGAGUCAGAUACCAGCCCUGCUUGGAGAUCAGAUGAAGACCCUCAGUGAUAACCAGACUCUCUGUGGGGACCAGGUGACCUUCAGUAGUGACCAGACCCUCACUGAUGGUCAUACAGUGACUUCCGGUAGCGAUGAGACCCUCUCUGGGGGCCAAAUGACAACCAGUCUAGACCUCUAUGGAGGGCAAAUGAUGACUUCCAUUGAUAACCAGACCCUCUGUGGGGAGCAGAUGACGACCUCCAGUGGUAACCAGGCCUUCUACGGGAGACAGAUGACGACCUCCACUGGUAACCAGACCCUCUGUGGAGAGCAGAUGACAACCUCCACUGGUAACCAGGCCCUCUAUGGGGGGCAGAUGACGACCUCCGCUAGUAACCAGACCCUCUGUGGAGAGCAGAUGACAACCUCCACUAGUAACCAGACCCUCUGUGGGGAGCAAGUGAUGACCUCCACUGGUAACCAAGCCCUCUGUGGAGGGCAGAUGACGACCUCCACUGGUAACCAGAACCUCUAUGGGGGGCAGAUGAUGACCUCCACUGGUAACCAGACCCUCUACUGGGGGCAGAUGAUGACCUCCACUGGUAACCAGAACCUCUGUGGAGAGCAAGUGAUGACCUCCACUGGUAACCAAGCCCUCUGUGGAGGGCAGAUGACGACCUCCACUGGUAACCAGAACCUCUAUGGGGGGCAGAUGAUGACCUCCACUGGUAACCAGACCCUCUACUGGGGGCAGAUGAUGACCUCCACUGGUAACCAGAACCUCUGUGGAGAGCAAGUGAUGACCUCCACUGGUAACCAAGCCCUCUGUGGAGGGCAGAUGACGACCUCCACUGGUAACCAGAACCUCUGUGGAGAGCAAGUGAUGACCUCCACUAGUAACCAGACCCUCUGUGGAGAGCAGACGACGACCUCCACUAGUAACCAGACCCUCUGUGGGGAGCAGGUGACGACCUCCACUGGUAACCAGGCCCUCUACGGGGGGCAGAUGAUGACCUCCACUGGUAACCAGACCCUCUACUGGGGGCAGAUGAUGACCUCCACUGGUAACCAGAACCUCUGUGGAGAGCAGAUGACAACCUCCACUGGUAACCAGGCCCUCUACGGGGGGCAGAUGACAACCUCUACUAGUAACCAGACCCUCUGUGGAGAGCAGAUGACGACCCCCACUAGUAACCAGACCCUCUGUGGGGAGCAGGUGACGACCUCCACUGGUAACCAGGCCCUCUACGGGGGGCAGAUCACGACCUCCACUAGUAACCAGACCCUCUGUGGAGAGCAGAUGACGACCUCCACUAGUAACCAGACCCUUUGUGGGGAGCAGGUGACGACCUCCACUGGUAACCAGGCCCUCUAUGGGGGGCAGAUGAUGACCUCCACUGGUAACCAGGCCCUCUACGGGGGGCAGAUGACAACCUCUGCUAGUAACCAGACCCUCUGUGGAGAGCAGAUGACAACCUCCACUAGUAACCAGACCCUCUGUGAGGAGCAGGUGAUGACCUCCACUGGUAACCAGGCCCUCUGUGGAGAGCAGAUGACAACCUCCACUGGUAACCAGGCCCUCUACGGGGGGCAGAUGACGACCUCCACUAGUAACCAGACCCUCUGUGGAGAGCAGACGACGACCUCCACUAGUAACCAGACCCUCUGUGGGGAGCAGGUGACGACCUCCACUGGUAACCAGGCCCUCUAUGGGGGGCAGAUGAUGACCUCCACUGGUAACCAGACCCUCUACUGGGGGCAGAUGAUGACCUCCACUGGUAACCAGAACCUCUGUGGAGAGCAGAUGACAACCUCCACUGGUAACCAGGCCCUCUACGGGGGGCAGAUGACGACCUCUACUAGUAACCAGACCCUCUGUGGAGAGCAGAUGACGACCCCCACUAGUAACCAGACCCUCUGUGGGGAGCAGGUGACGACCUCCACUGGUAACCAGGCCCUCUACAGGGGGCAGAUCACGACCUCCACUAGUAACCAGACCCUCUGUGGAGAGCAGAUGACGACCUCCACUAGUAACCAGACCCUCUGUGGGGAGCAGGUGACGACCUCCACUGGUAACCAGGCCCUCUAUGGGGGGCAGAUGAUGACCUCCACUGGUAACCAGAACCUCUACGGGGGGCAGAAUAUGACCUCCACUGAUAACCAGGCCCUCUAUGGAGGCCAGAUGGCAACAUAUAGUGGCAACCAGACCCUCUAUGGGGACCAGAUGCUGACUCUUCAGGUGGGCAAUAUGACAACGCUCACUGAUGACCACAGCCUUUAUGGGGGAUAUAUGAUGUCCCAUCAGUUCUCAUCAUUGCCAUACCCAGGAUUCCUAUGCUUUUCAAGUUCCCAUUUGAUUCAAGGACAACUCCCAAAACAGAAGACACAGAGCUGCCAGUUCUGGAAGAAUCCUGAGGUUUCAAGGCCCUAUGUCUGCACUUACGAGGACUGCAAGAUGUCUUAUUCAAAGGCUUGCCACCUCCGAACCCACAUGCGCAAGCACACCGGGGAGAAGCCCUAUGUAUGCGAUGUAGAGGGAUGUACGUGGAAAUUUGCCCGCUCAGAUGAGCUCAACAGACACAAGAAAAGGCACACUGGGGAAAGGCCCUACCUGUGUUCAAUAUGCAGCAAGAAUUUUGCAAGAUCUGAUCACCUAAAGCAGCAUGCAAAGGUCCACAACAUUCGCCCAGGAUUAUGA